AGAGGCAGAGGGAGGAGCCUCGGGGGGAAGGAGAGGGAGGGGACCGUCAGGAAGCCGCGAACGCCGCCGAGUGUCUGCACACCUCGCUCUGCCUGCCAUGGCUGGUUAAAGAACCAUCCGGAUCGCAGCGCGGGGGGAGGGCCGGGUGGGGGGAGCAGCGGCCGCGCGUGAGGCCGAGGGAGGGGCGGCGGCGCGAGCGGCGGCGGCGGCGGUUCCAGCAUGAAGAGGAGAGCUGGCCUGGGGGGCAGCAUGAGGUCAGUGGUGGGCUUCUUGUCCCAGCGGGGCUUGCAUGGGGACCCCCUGCUCACUCAGGACUUUCAGAGGAGACGCCUGCGGGGCUGCAGAAACCUCUACAAGAAGGACCUCCUCGGCCACUUCGGCUGUGUCAAUGCCAUUGAAUUCUCCAACAAUGGAGGCCAGUGGCUGGUCUCAGCUAUCCCCUUUUCCAGGGCACAGUGAGGCCAGCAGAUAUUGAGUAAACCGGAGAAAAUCAGGAAGGAGAAAAGGAGGAGAUGACCGCCGGGUUCUGCUAUGGCACAUGGAACAAGCCAUCCACUCCAGGGUCAAGCCCAUACAGCUGAAAGGAGAGCACCAUUCCAACAUUUUUUGCCUGGCUUUCAACAGUGGGAACACUAAAGUGUUCUCUGGAGGCAAUGAUGAGCAAGUUAUCCUCCAUGAUGUUGAAAGCAGUGAGACAUUGGACGUGUUUGCUCAUGAAGAUGCAGUAUAUGGCUUGUCUGUGAGCCCAGUGAAUGACAACAUUUUUGCCAGUUCCUCAGAUGAUGGCCGGGUUCUCAUUUGGGACAUUCGGGAAUCCCCCCAUGGAGAGCCCUUCUGCCUGGCAAACUAUCCAUCAGCCUUUCAUAGUGUCAUGUUUAACCCUGUGGAGCCCAGGUUGUUGGCCACAGCCAAUUCAAAGGAAGGAGUGGGACUCUGGGACAUUCGAAAACCUCAGAGUUCUCUCCUGCGCUAUGGUGGAAACCUGUCCCUCCAAAGUGCCAUGAGUGUACGAUUCAACAGCAACGGGACCCAGCUCCUGGCCCUGAGGCGACGCCUGCCCCCUGUGCUCUAUGACAUCCAUUCCCGCCUGCCUGUGUUUCAGUUUGACAAUCAGGGUUACUUCAACUCAUGCACCAUGAAAAGCUGCUGUUUUGCAGGAGAUCGUGACCAGAAACCAGAGGCUGAGGGAAAGGUGAUUUUCUUCAGGUUGUGUUUAGCAACAAAGCCUAUCUUCAUGGACCUUAGAAGACCCAGAACAAAGACCUCUAGCCAACAUUAUAUCCUUUCGGGCUCUGAUGACUUCAACCUGUACAUGUGGAGAAUUCCUGCAGAUCCAGAAGCAGGUGGCAUUGGUAGGGUGGUCAACGGAGCCUUCAUGGUGCUGAAAGGGCAUCGAUCUAUUGUUAACCAAGUCCGAUUUAAUCCCCACACCUACAUGAUCUGCUCUUCUGGUGUAGAAAAGAUUAUCAAGAUCUGGAGCCCAUACAAGCAGCCAGGAUGUACUGGAGACCUCGACGGUCGGAUUGAGGACGAUUCCCGCUGCCUCUAUACCCAUGAAGAGUACAUCAGCCUUGUGCUGAACAGUGGGAGUGGCCUGUCGCAUGACUACGCCAACCAGUCGGUCCAGGAAGACCCCCGGAUGAUGGCCUUCUUUGACUCACUGGUACGCCGAGAGAUCGAGGGCUGGAGCUCUGACUCAGACAGUGACCUCAGUGAGAGUACUAUCCUCCAACUGCACGCUGGGGUCAGCGAGCGCUCAGGCUACACUGACUCAGAGUCUUCGGCCUCAUUGCCUCGCUCCCCGCCUCCCACAGUAGAUGAGUCUGCCGACAACGCCUUCCACCUGGGGCCCCUGCGGGUCACCACCACAAACACAGUAGCCUCAACUCCACCAACACCCACGUGUGAGGAUGCAGCCUCUCGCCAGCAGCGUCUGUCUGCUCUGCGGCGCUACCAAGACAAACGCCUCCUGGCCCUUUCCAAUGAGUCCGAUUCUGAGGAGAAUGUCUGUGAGGUGGAACUAGACACAGAUCUCUUUCCCCGGCCACGGUCACCCAGCCCCGAAGAUGAAUCCAGCAGUUCCAGCAGCUCUAGCAGCUCUGAGGAUGAGGAGGAGCUGAAUGAACGCCGAGCCUCUACCUGGCAGCGGAAUGCCAUGCGGCGCCGACAGAAGACAACCCGAGAAGACAAGCCCAGUGCCCCAAUCAAGCCCACCAACACUUACAUUGGAGAAGACAACUAUGAUUACCCCCAGAUCAAAGUGGAUGACCUCUCCUCCUCCCCAACCUCGUCCCCUGAGCGGAGCACUUCCACGCUAGAGAUUCAACCAAGCCGGGCAUCACCAACUUCUGACAUAGAAUCAGUUGAGCGAAAAAUUUAUAAAGCUUACAAGUGGCUCCGCUACUCUUAUAUCUCCUACUCAAAUAACAAAGAUGGAGAGACCUCCUUGGUGACCGGGGAGGCAGAUGAAGGGAGAGCAGGAACCAGCCACAAAGACAACCCAGCCCCUUCUUCCAGUAAGGAAGCCUGUCUAAACAUAGCAAUGGCCCAGAGGAACCAGGACCUGCCACCUGAAGGCUGCAGCAAGGACACUUUUAAAGAAGAGACUCCUAGAACUCCCAGCAAUGGCCCAGGCCAUGAGCACAGCAGCCAUGCUUGGGCAGAGGUGCCAGAGGGUACCUCUCAGGACACUGGCAAUAGCGGCUCUGUAGAGCACCCUUUUGAAACCAAGAAGCUCAAUGGAAAGGCCCUGAGCAGUCGGGCUGAGGAGCCGCCUUCUCCUCCUGUCCCCAAGGCAUCUGGCUCCACUCUCAACAGCGGGUCUGGCAACUGUCCCAGGACCCAGUCUGAUGACAGUGAGGAGAGGAGCCUCGAAACCAUCUGUGCCAACCACAACAAUGGACGCUUACACCCUCGUCCCCCUCACCCUCACAAUAACGGGCAGAACUUGGGGGAGCUGGAGGUGGUGGCCUACUCUUCCCCAGGACACUCAGACACUGACCGUGAUAACUCGUCCCUGACAGGGACACUCCUACACAAAGAUUGUUGCGGGUCUGAAAUGGCCUGUGAGACCCCCAAUGCUGGAACAAGAGAGGACCCCACUGACACCCCAGCCACAGAUAGUAGCAGGGCUGUUCAUGGCCACAGUGGCCUCAAAAGGCAACGAAUUGAAUUGGAAGAUACAGAUUCAGAGAAUUCCUCCUCAGAGAAGAAAUUAAAAACAUGAUAAAUACAAAGGGAAAACAAAAAGCUACAAAAGUAGCCUUACAAAAAAAAAAAAAUUGUUUAGUGAAUACAGAGGAAAGGAAAAACAAGUAUUAAAGGCACAUGAAACCAGGGCCUGAAAUUUUGUGUCUGAUGCUGCUCCCUUCUAUCCAACAUUCAACAACGGGUCUGAAUGUCUAGCUGGCCAUUGGCUUGUGCUGUGUUAAGAAAGGGGAAAAAAAAAUAACCCAAGUGACUCCUUUCUAGUGAGACGUGAGCGUAGUGUGCCGCGCAAGGCUCUGUGGAAGUAAAUCUUUGUUGAGACGUUCGACUUGUUCUUGUGUACGCACAAUGGCACGUGUGCGCUUAUUGUCUCAUAAGACCUUCCUUUUAGUUCUCCAUCAGAAAGGACCUAUGAAUUUGUACUUUUUGCCAUCUCACCCUGUUUACAUGCCAUAGGUGUUCUGGUCUGGAUGAUGGGUGCCUGUUAAAUCAGGUUGUGCUGCCAGUGAGUUGUAGAUUUAUGCUGGAAGAAUGGAGAAUGGAAACAGGCCUUCAGCCCAUUGGCUGCGCUGGAGAGGAAAGCAUGGUUCCUUUCUUAAAGAAAUCUUCCAUGUUUUCUCUAAGUAACACUUCUUUAUUGAGCAUUUAAUGUGGACAUACUAUAAAAAAGAAUUUUUAAUGCUAAUGAGAGGUUUAGCACUUAAGAUCAGAUUCAAGAGAAUAUAGAUUCCUGAUAAAUUUCACUGUUUGCAAAUUGAGCAGUGCUGCAACAUGUACUGUAUGAAGGCCAUAAAAUAGAGCUAGUCAUGGAUAACAGACUUUAACCAGUUAGGUGCUAGAUCCUAAGAGGCACUCACAAGGCCAGCAGGUGCUUCCUUGGCUCCCAUGAUCGAUCGAGGCAUAGUGAAAGAAGGGCAAAGACAGCUUUCCAGAGCUUUGUGCUCAGGCUACUAAAGUAGUUGUUAUAGGUGUGUUAACGAAGAAGCUUAGUGAGGAGCAGAAUGUGGUACUAUAUUCAUUUAACUCAACCCAGAACCAUUGGUCAGAAUUGGUGGGACUGGCAUCUUCCCUCAGACUUGCAGUUGAUAGAGGCUGUGGUGUUCUCACUAGACUUUGCAGAGCAGUAGGCAUCUCAAGGUAACAGAUUCUUAUUGAGUAGGUCUAUUAGGAGUCAGAAGGUGUUGGGGAGGAGUCUCUGGCUUAUGACUCCUGGUUCCCAUUAGUCUUAAGUCUUCUGGUUCCCAUAAAAGACUCAGUUUUAUUGAGGUAGAUACAGGUUUAGAAGAGAAAAGAGCAACAGAUUUUCAGCGUUGCAGUCACUCGGUUAUCUAUGAAGGGUUGUGCAAAACAGGAAGGUCUGGGAAUGACCAGAUAUCUUGUUGGCAUAAAUGUUAUGAAAAGGCAGAAUACUGGCAAGAAAUGAGGAAGAGAGAGAAAAACAAUAUAACUUUCUUGAGUGCAAAGGUGCUAGACAACUAGGAGCCCAGCUGGGAUUGGUGUAGGGAGGGCCGAACGCUGACUAGUGUGGCCUCACUGCCCCAGGCUUCCUUUCAGAGGAAGGCCUGUCCUGCUGGAACUGGAGCCAAGGGGAGGCUGCCUAUGAAGGCAGAAGAUGUGGAUGAAUUCAGGCACUGGGGGUGGGGGGGUUAUUUAUAAACACAAGGUGGUUGGUUUAAGCCAAAAGGAGAUACCAUCCUGAUAAGCUCUGUGAAAGAGAAGAUGUGCCUGGUGUGUGUAAUGCGGCUGGGGUAUGAAAACACUGAGAAGGAGAUGAAGGAGUGUGUGUAGCAUGGGGGUGUGUACAACUUAACACCUGGACUUUUACUGGGGGAGUGGGAAAGUGAUUCUGUAACCAACAUUAGAAUUACUUUGGAUUUGUAAUCAGAUUGGUUCUAUGAUUUGUCUUUGACUAUUCACAGAUAAUUGUAAAUGCUGGUUUUAUAAGCCCAAGUCAUUUUACAUUUGCUUUUCCAAAAUGUAUUAAAUUGGAAUUUUUUAAUCCUUUAUAUACAAAAAAAAUACGAUCACUCAGUGUGUGUUUCUCUUCCCCUUCUUAGUCAGCACACCCAGUCCUUUAUUUUAUUCUAUUCUAUUUAUUUUAUUUUAAUAAGUACUUAGCCUCUUCUGACUUCUCAAAGGACAAUCGGAUACAUAUCUUCCUGAAAAGAAGUAGUUAAAGUUCCCUUGGGAACUAGCUACUUGGUAGUUACAAUUCCCAAAUGCAGAACUUGGUCUUUUCAUGUUAAAAGCCUUAAUCUCAUUUGGGUACUCAAAAGAGAAAUCAGAGUUUAUUCUGGUUAACUUGAGAAGCCAAGAAAGAUCAUUUUUAGCAAGUAUGCCUUCCAUCCUUGGCAGAGGCUUCCCAGCAUCCUAGGCUCAGCUUACCGGGUGAUAGGCCCCAUAAGACACACACAUGAGCAGGGUGAGAAAUGCUUGCUUUAUAGCUGCUCCACCCUCAUCUCCAGAGAUUUUGUGUCUAUGGUUGUGGGUCUGGAAACCUGGCAGGAACCACUUCUAGAGUACCUUUGCCUAAACUCUUUUAGAAUUGAGGCCCCAACUUUGAUGGCACAUUUAAUACCCAAUUUCUUCCAUAAUAGAUAUUUUUAAUAGCAGGACAGAUGGCACUGAUUAGAUCAAGAACUAUUUGGAAGUGCCUCUUAUGUUUUUUUCCUGCAUUCUGUACAUAAAGUUUUAAGUGGCAGGUCCAGAUAUGUAAAAUCAUUUCUCUCUAUUUUCCAGCUGGUUUUGUUAAUGAUUCUCUAGGACAGCAGGUAAAUGAGUUAAGUUGUUGGCUUGGGGCAAGUGAAGUUUGUGACUAUGCUUGAUUUAAUAAGCUGAGAGUCUCUUGUUUGUCUGUCAAGGUGCCUUCCUCUGCUGAAGCCUUACCUCCUUCUCACCCAGUAACGGUUAACUCUUCUCUUGUGUAUAUGCAAAUAAACCUAUUAUUCACUUCUCACGUCUUCCUCUUCUCUUCCAGGGAAGACUUGGUUGCUUA